UAGAGACAGGCAUCUCACCAUGUUUCCCAGACUGGCCUCGAACUCCUGGGCUCAAGCAAUCCACCCACCUCAGCCUCCCGAAGUGCUGGGGUUAUAAGUGUGAGCCACUGUGCCCUGUGAAAUUGGCUCCUUUUUAUGUGAGGUGCAAACCUCUGCAUCCCACUGGCCUGGUCUGAGCACCUCAGAAGUCCUGGGUGCUGCUGAAGUUGCCAAUAUUUGAAAUUAUAUUGUUUUCAAAUCUUCAAAGUAAGUUGAGAACUCAAAGCCAAGUUUCUGAAACCCAGCUGCUGAUUGAAUCACCAGGGUGCUUGUUAAUACUACAUGUUUUCCAAGCCCUUCUUCCCUGGGACAUCUGGUUUGGGGCCUAGGCUCUCUCUUUUCAACAAACAUUUCACAUGAAUCUGGUGAUUAUCAAGAUUUAGAGAAAUCUGUUGUAAUUCAGUUGUUUUCAUCUUUUGAAUCCAAGUAUUUAUUUCAUGAUGAAUUUGAAAUCCAGGCAGUAGGCUUAAACUAAACAAUGUGUUCGCCUGUAAGAUCCCCCAUAAGGCAUUUGGAAGAGAUCUUUUCAGGGAGAGGGUGGGAGGAUGCCGGGGGGUCUUUUGCAUUUGAGUUUGAAGGGAGCUAACCCAUCAGUGUUUUUGAGAAAGCUCACCUUGUCCCUGUUACCUGGAGUCCAAGGCUUCUGCCACUAAGCCCGGCCAAGCAUUCGGGUGGGACAGCCGCCACCAAGCCAGGUGUCUGGGGUCUCAGUGUCCUGGAUGACUCCAUCUGCAAGACCAAGGCGAGUUUCUCCAGGGCCACGAGGCAGCGCCUGGCUCCGGCAGCUGGGCACGUCCAGGGCAGAGGCUGUGCUUCUGGAUUGGGGCGUCCUCACCAUGCCCCAGCCCAGGCGUCUCCCCCAGGCCUUCCUUCUGGAGAGACACCUUAUUCGUGCCUGUCUCUUAAAGCCUCAAGUUUGAUUGAAGAAGCAGAAGUUGGCAUAGACACCUUUGAGCAUUCAAGCUCUCGCCGGGCCUGCUGCAGGCAUUUCAAGGCAUCUUAGCCCAUCGUUUAAUUUAGGACAGAGGCCACGGAGAGGCACCGCUGGAGCAGUACACCGCACACCACAGGGUGGCUGCACUUUUUGGGUGGUGGGGUGGGGAUGGGGGCAGGUAUGAUCAAUCAUCCAAACCAGGGCAUUUUUAAGAGUAAAAGGAGGCUCUACUGAUAACAUGCUGCAACAACAGAUGUGACUAGGAACGGCCGGUGACAUGGGGAGGGCCUAUCACCCUAUUCUUGGGGGCUGCUUCUUCACAGUGAUCAUGAAGCCUAGCAGCAAAUCCCACCUCCCCACACGCACACGGCCAGCCUGGAGCCCACAGAAGGGUCCUCCUGCAGCCAGUGGAGCUUGGUCCAGCCUCCAGUCCACCCCUAACAGGCUUAAGGAUAGAAACGACACAUAACACCGGGAAAAGCCAUGCUGUCAAGCAUCUCAGAAUCUCAACCCCAGAGGCAGUCUUUAGGGACUGGGGUGGGCUCAGGAAGCUGUAUUAUUUCAAAGGACGCAGUGUUUCCACAGCUCAGCCCAGAGCUGCUGGAGUUCACACGGCCCACCAGAACCUGCUGACUUCAAAAUCAUCACCACCAAGGGGCCAGGAGGUGGCGCUGUGGGGCAACAGAAAACAGAAAACAGCUGCUCCUUGAACUUGGAUUCCCAGCAGCUCCCCCAAGCGCCCACAGGGGCUGCAUUCCUCCCUGCUGGACACCUGUAACUACAACAUUAAAACAGGGCGCAAGCAAGGAACACAAACACUGGGAAAGCUGUGCCUUUAAAAAAAAAAAAAAAAAGGAGGGUAAAAAAGCUUAAGGUUAAUGUUUUGAAACCUGACCCAGCCAGGGCCUAAUGCAGACCUUGUCCAGCUAGUAAGUGGGCCUCUGGGGGUCUUCAUUGAGUGAACCUUCAGAGUGCUGGUGUUUCACCAAGGCCUUCCAUAGAGGACGCGGCAGGCUCUGCAGGAAGCAGCUUCGAUGGCCGAUGGCCAAGAAAGGAAGGGAAAACCCCUGGACUGGUCGCUGGGCACCCAGUCCCCCUACCCCCGUGCCUUCCCUUCCAGUGCCUUUCCCUCUUUCCCUCGGUGGUAGCUUUGCCUGACAGUGCAGACCUCGCCUGACGUCAACACUAGGUUCUUUAUGCUCAUGUGGUUUUAUUUUUGUUUUCUCCUAUCAAGAGUGGUCAGAAAAUCUCUGUUCCAUGUCAGGAACAAGGAAAAUCUUUUGGAAUUUUUUUGGUUUUUUUCUUUUUUUUAGCAUGACUUGAUCAGAUAGGUAGGAUAAUGUUGCCCCCUUGGCCCAAGUGCAGAGUGACAAAAGGGACCAACACUAAAAGGAUCCCUGAGAUCCUGGGAUACUUCCUCUUCAUGUUCAUUGUGGGGGCCGGGGACAUCACCCUGACAGGUGGGUCCCCAGGCCCCAGAAAGCUCAUUUCCGCAUCCCUGGGUGCAGGGGGAGUUCACGGGGUCUCUGCCUGUUGGUUUGGGAUGCGUCUCCUCAAGGCACUCACUGUCCAGAGAGAACAAAAAUAAAACCAGGUCUGCUCUCUGGCUCUGUCAUCUGGGCACGUUCGGAGCCAAAAGCCUUGACCUUCUGAAAGUUCACUGAAAAAUCAUCUCGUAAAAGGCAGAUUCAUUGGACAAAAGAUUUAGAAAUGUGUUUACCGUGUAUACAUGGGAGCCUUCAGAAUACAGACCCACAGAUGCAGGGAAAUUGUCCAUUUUUAUGCUUAGGUUCAAGAAAGGGUGGACUGCGUGUGGAAAGAAGAUUAUAUAACAAGGCCGGACCUGCUGCUAAUAGGCUGAGUGGGGAACCUAGCAAGGUCUGUCUGCCUGGAUUCUUCUUGGCCUUUCCUCCUCCGAGAAUGGGGCGGGAUGCUCUCUGGAGUGAGGGUCUUAUGACCUAAAGUCAAACAAGGAAGGUCAGAUAAUUUCUUUUUUUAUUUUUAAUGUUUUUUUUUAGAGAUGGGUUCUCACUAUGUUGCCCAGGCUGGUUUUGAACUCCUGGGCUCAAGCAGUCCUCCCACUUGGGCCUCUCAAAGUGCUGGGAUUACAAGCAUAAACCGUGCAUGCCCAGCCAGAUAAUUUCUUUAUGGCUAGUUUUUACACAGAAAAGUAGAGGGAAAGAGUGAUAUUUGUAUGUUUUAUGGCUGGCUUUGGGAGAAAGGGAUACUGGUUUCUAUGUCCUGCCUUGGGGAAGAGGGAUUCUAGUUUCUGUGGCUGGCCUUGGGGAAGAAUGGGCCUGAGAGACAAGAGGGCAGGAGAAGGUCAGAGAGAAACUUUGCUUCUGAGGCUGCUGCUGAGGCCCUCAUUUGGGGCAUUGUUUUCUGAGCCCCAGCAGCAUUGCCAGCCAGGCAGGCAUCCGCUGAGUGUGUAAAAAUAGACCUGUCAGAGCUCAGACACGGGCACCUGCAGGCCCCUUUAAAACCCUUGACAGCUUUUAUCUUUAAGAGAAAGAUUUAAGUAAAAAAUGUACCAUGCUGCCUCCCCCAUCUUUCCUUCCACUGGGGAAACUGAGGCCCUCUGAGCCCAGGCAGGCAGCCGGUCCCCUUGACUCACCCCAGCAUCUUCCCAGACAUUCCUAAACAGGCAGCAAAGCAGUGAAUGGCAGUGGCAGCUUCAGGCAGGACAGGCAGUAACAGCGUGUGCUUGUCACCUGAUCUCAGCUGUUUGUUAUAAAGUCCGUCGUUCAGAUUUCCAGUUUUGCCAACUGGUUGACUAUUUCUAUCUCUGUAUUAUAAAUGGAAAACUGUACAAUGAGACUUAAUUUUCCAACCCAUGUAAAAGAUCACUGCUGGCUCAGGACAGAGCCUGAGAACCCAGAGCUUCCCAAGGCCCAGUCGAUGGUAGAAUUGUAAGCUGGUGUGGACAUCACGGAGGAGGGUGUACGGCACUCGGGGGCGGAUGAAAGGAGGUGCACAGUGAGGUCUCCAUCUCGCAGGAGGCUUUGGAAGAUGCGUCGGUGAUUGAUUGAGUACAUCCGCCGAAUGCUCGCCAGGUGCCGGGUCCUGGGCUGUCCUGAGGGUAGUGCUGUGGAAGAGCCAGGCCCUGCUGUCCCCACUUGGGGACAGUCAGCACAGCCAGUCCAGUGAAUAGGGACACUUGUGCCUCUGGGAGUGAAAACCACAAGGGAGGAGUUUCCUGCAGAGGGGCCCCAGGCCCGAGAGAUGAGGAUAGGAUCCCCACGGGGAUCACAGGUGGGCCAGUCAGGGAAAUGUCUAAAACAGAAACCACGCGGUCGUUUCACAUAAGGAACUGGUUGAAAUGCUGUUAACUGAGAAUGGGAAAAGGAGAUACUGAGGUAUCAGAGGUCAUAACUGCAGGAGUGCCUGCAUCCCCCACAACUACCAGGGGUGCAAGCAAAGGGCAGAGGCUGGGAUUAAUAGAAACAGGCAGCUCCAAGGAGGCCACCCAGGGGUGGGACCCAGCCCUCCAAGGCAGGGGUGCUGCCCACUGGUGCCCAUGUCUCAGGGGCCGUGAUGAAGCUGGACCAGCUGUCAGGGUCAAGGGCUUGGUGCUGGAAGCCACAGGAAGGGGAACAUUCCUUCUCCUUCCUUUUCCCACUCUCACUCACUGCGAGCCGAGCCCUCACAGAGGAGCAGGCAAGGCAGAGGUGUGGUGUGCAGGGCCAGCUCCCACAUCACAGAGCAGAGAGUGAAGGUGGCUCUGAGGCCACCCUGGGCCCUGCACCCGCAGUCCUGCUUCCCUUUGCAGUUGACAAUGCACACUCCAAUGCACCAAUGCCUGCUUGUUCACACCUGUGACCCGUGAGGCACAGAGAGCAAGGGGCAGGUCCCAGGGCAAGGGUGUCCAGGGGCAGCAAGGCCUGGCUGGGCCCAGAGGAUCUGACCUCCACAGUGCCAGCUGUGCCCUCAGCCCCUGGAGUAGAAAGGUGGAUGGUCCACGGGGCCUGCUGGCUCUAAACCCUGGGGUCCCUUUCCUAAAUCACUUGCCACAGCCACAGCACCGGCCAAGCCAAGGUCAGUAGGAGAAAGGAGGGAGAGACGGUGGGGCUGUGCUAGGGAGGCCAGGCCCAGGAGGUCAGUGUGAGGAAGGAGCCCUGGGGGGCAGAGAAAGGAGAGGGGGCAUGAGGGCUGGGCCUCACCUCCCUUCCUGUAGUGAUGAGGUCAGGCCUGCUGACCAGCAAAUGCUAUGAGCCUGCAGGUGAAACCAUGUGUUUGGGAGAACAUGACUUAGCUCUAGGCCUCAUUCACACUCCACAGCUCCAGGGUCUUCCUACUGCCCAAUAAGCACAAUCCUGCAGACAUGGUCAGACCUGUUGGUAACAUUGAUUGGUAACAUUGGCAACUGAUUGGUAAUGUUGAUGCAGAUUACCGGUUUUUAUACUGUAAUUCAGACCAGCUCUAAGUGAUGUUUGGAUAGGUAUACGAAAGGCCAGCAGAGAGCCUUCGCUGGAUGUUUCUCACUGGGCCUGAACUGAUAUCUGAAGAGAGAAGUGGAGACAGCGACCAGACAGAUGAGGAUGGAGAACCUGGCUCAGAGGCCCAGGCCCAGGCCCAGCCCUUUGGCAGCAAAAAAAAGCGCCUCCUCUCCGUCCACGACUUCGACUUCGAGGGAGACUCAGAUGACUCCACUCAGCCUCAAGGUCACUCCCUGCACCUGUCCUCAGUCCCUGAGGCCAGGGACAGCCCACAGUCCCUCACAGAUGAGUCCUGCUCAGAGAAGGCAGCCCCUCACAAGGCUGAGGGCCUGGAGGAGGCUGAUACUGGGGCCUCUGGGUGCCACUCCCAUCCGGAAGAGCAGCCGACCAGCAUCUCACCUUCCAGACACGGCGCCCUGGCUGAGCUCUGCCCGCCUGGAGGCUCCCACAGGAUGGCCCUGGGGACUGCUGCUGCACUCGGGUCGAAUGUCAUCAGGAAUGAGCAGCUGCCCCUGCAGUACUUGGCCGAUGUGGACACCUCUGAUGAGGAAAGCAUCCGGGCUCACGUGAUGGCCUCCCACCAUUCCAAGCGGAGAGGCCGGGCGUCUUCUGAGAGUCAGAUCUUUGAGCUGAAUAAGCAUAUUUCAGCUGUGGAAUGCCUGCUGACCUACCUGGAGAACACAGUUGUGCCUCCCUUGGCCAAGGGUCUAGGUGCUGGAGUGCGCACGGAGGCCGAUGUAGAGGAGGAGGCCCUGAGGAGGAAGCUGGAGGAGCUGACCAGCAACGUCAGUGACCAGGAGACCUCGUCCGAGGAGGAGGAAGCCAAGGACGAAAAGGCAGAGCCCAACAGGGACAAAUCAGUUGGGCCUCUCCCCCAGGCGGACCCGGAGGUGGGCACGGCUGCCCAUCAAACCAACAGACAGGAAAAAAGCCCCCAGGACCCUGGGGACCCCGUCCAGUACAACAGGACCACAGAUGAGGAGCUGUCAGAGCUGGAGGACAGAGUGGCAGUGACGGCCUCAGAAGUCCAGCAGGCAGAGAGCGAGGUUUCAGACAUUGAAUCCAGGAUUGCAGCCCUGAGGGCCGCAGGGCUCACGGUGAAGCCCUCGGGAAAGCCCCGGAGGAAGUCAAACCUCCCGAUAUUUCUCCCUCGAGUGGCUGGGAAACUUGGCAAGAGACCAGAGGACCCAAAUGCAGACCCUUCAAGUGAGGCCAAGGCAAUGGCUGUGCCCUAUCUUCUGAGAAGAAAGUUCAGUAAUUCCCUGAAAAGUCAAGGUAAAGAUGAUGAUUCUUUUGAUCGGAAAUCAGUGUACCGAGGCUCGCUGACACAGAGAAACCCCAACGCGAGGAAAGGAAUGGCCAGCCACACCUUCGCGAAACCUGUGGUGGCCCACCAGUCCUAACGGGACAGGACAGAGAGACAGAGCAGCCCUGCACUGUUUUCCCUCCACCACAGCCAUCCUGUCCCUCAUUGGCUCUGUGCUUUCCACUAUACACAGUCACCGUCCCAAUGAGAAACAAGAAGGAGCACCCUCCACAUGGACUCCCACCUGCAAGUGGACAGCGACAUUCAGUCCUGCACUGCUCACCUGGGUUUACUGAUGACUCCUGGCUGCCCCACCAUCCUCUCUGAUCUGUGAGAAACAGCUAAGCUGCUGUGACUUCCCUUUAGGACAAUGUUGUGUAAAUCUUUGAAGGACACACCGAAGACCUUUAUACUGUGAUCUUUUACCCCUUUCACUCUUGGCUUUCUUAUGUUGCUUUCAUGAAUGGAAUGGAAAAAAGAUGACUCAGUUAAGGCACCAGCCAUAUGUGUAUUCUUGAUGGUCUAUAUCGGGGUGUGAGCAGAUGUUUGCGUAUUUCUUGUGGGUGUGACUGGAUAUUAGACAUCCGGACAAGUGACUGAACUAAUGAUCUGCUGAAUAAUGAAGGAGGAAUAGACACCCCAGUCCCCACCCUACGUGCACCCGCUCUGCAAGUUCCCAUGUGAUCUGUAGACCAGGGGAAAUUACACUGCGGUCAAGGGCAGAGCCUGCACAUGACAGCAAGUGAGCAUUUGAUAGAUGCUCAGAUGCUAGUGCAGAGAGCCUGCUGGGAGACGAAGAGACAGCAGGCAGAGCUCCAGAUGGGCAAGGAAGAGGCUUGGUUCUAGCCUGGCUCUGCCCCUCACUGCAGUGGAUCCAGUGGGGCAGAGGACAGAGGGUCACAACCAAUGAGGGAUGUCUGCCAAGGAUGGGGGUGCAGAGGCCACAGGAGUCAGCUUGCCACUCGCCCAUUGGUUACAUAGAUGAUCUCUCAGACAGGCUGGGACUCAGAGUUAUUUCCUAGUAUCGGUGUGCCCCAUCCAGUUUUAAGUGGAGCCCUCCAAGACUCUCCAGAGCUGCCUUUGAACAUCCUAACAGUAAUCACAUCUCACCCUCCCUGAGGUUCACUUUAGACAGGACCCAAUGGCUGCACUGCCUUUGUCAGAGGGGGUGCUGAGAGGAGUGGCUUCUUUUAGAAUCAAACAGUAGAGACAAGAGUCAAGCCUUGUGUCUUCAAGCAUUGACCAAGUUAAGUGUUUCCUUCCCUCUCUCAAUAAGACACUUCCAGGAGCUUUCCAAUCUCUCACUUAAAACUAAGGUUUGAAUCUCAAAGUGUUGCUGGGAGGCUGAUACUCCUGCAACUUCAGGAGACCUGUGAGCACACAUUAGCAGCUGUUUCUCUGACUCCUUGUGGCAUCAGAUAAAAACGUGGGAGUUUUUCCAUAUAAUUCCCAGCCUUACUUAUAAAUUCUAUUCUUUGAAAAAAUUAUUCAGGCUAGGUAAGGUGGCUCAUACCUAUAAUCCCAGCCCUUUGAGAGGCCAAGGUGGGAGAAUUGCUUGAGGCCAGGAGUUUGAGACCUCCUGGGCAACAUAGUGAGAUCCCAUCUCUACAAAAAACAAAACAAAAAAAUUACCCAAGCAUGAUGGUAUAUGCCUGUAGUCGUACCUACUUACUUAGGAGGCUGAGGCAGGAGGAUCACUUGAGCCCUGGAGGUUGGGGCUGCAGUGAGCCAUGAUCGCAUCACUAUACUCGAGCCUGGGCAACAGAGUGAGACCUUGUCUCUUAAAAAAAUUAAUAAUAAAUAAAUGAAAAUAAUUCUUCAGAGUUC